UGUUUCUUGACACUUCAGGUGUACACACACGUGUGAGUGUACUAGGAGGUGUUCUACAGUGUGUUUCUGUAGGUCGCAGUGAGAAAAAUUUGAAAAGCGUUGUCUCCUGUGCCCUUCUAUUUGCCCUCUUGCCUUUCUUUGCCUGAGUUUUCAGUCACUUAAAAUUGUCUGAGGAUGCAGUUAGCAUGCCAGGAAUAUACAGUAAAGAACAAGGUGGAUCUUCUUCACGGAGGUUACUGUGUGAGACGAAAGACAGUUCACUGUUCAUCACUGGAAAUACUGUACGUGCUACUGAAAAACAAGGAUUUUAUUGAGGAUCUAUCUUGGGAUCCCAUGGCUUUCUUUACUGGGCUCUGGGGCCCCUUCACCUGUGUAAGCAGAGUGCUGAGCCAUCACUGUUUCAGCACCACUGGGAGUCUGAGUGCGAUUCAGAAGAUGACGCGGGUACGAGUGGUGGACAACAGUGCCCUGGGGAACAGCCCAUACCAUCGGGCUCCUCGCUGCAUCCAUGUCUAUAAGAAGAAUGGAGUGGGCAAGGUGGGCGACCAGAUACUACUGGCCAUCAAGGGACAGAAGAAAAAGGCGCUCAUUGUGGGGCACUGCAUGCCUGGCCCCCGAAUGACCCCCAGAUUCGACUCCAACAACGUGGUCCUCAUUGAGGACAACGGGAACCCUGUGGGGACACGAAUUAAGACACCCAUCCCCACCAGCCUGCGCAAGCGGGAAGGCGAGUAUUCCAAGGUGCUGGCCAUUGCUCAGAACUUUGUGUGAGUUGAGCCCAGGCCUCUGGUUGCAGGACUCGUGAAUGGAGCAGUUCUGAGAACCACCCUUUUGCUAAGGGAGCUUGGGAGCCACAUGGCUGCUCCCUUCACACUGGGUAACAGUGUAGUAUCCUGUGAGAGAAUAAAUGUAUUCAUUUAUGUGUUUUUCCAGAGCUUUCUGGGAUGUGGGAAAAUAAAUUACACUGAAGCAGUUGAAAGGUGGCUUACCCGAGUCUGGCCACACGGGGUAGCAUUCUUUACAUGGAGCAGCCUUGGUGCCAGGGUCUGAGCCCUUGCUUUUCUGGUUUGGACCCUAUAAGUUCAUCCAGGACUGUCAGGCCCUGGAAAACUGAGGUACACACCAAAUGCCAAUUUAUAAAUGUACCAUGGCUCUAACCAAAA